GUCGUUGUCCCGCGAGCCGCCGACCAGGCCUCGAACGGGAUGGCAGAGGAGGUGAGGAGGGAGGAAGCGUCCGGAGUGGGGCGGGCCCGGACUCCGACCCCCGGGGCGCUUCGAGCCCCCCAGCUGGUCACCGAGGCACCGCCGCUUCACCCAGGCCAGUAGCCGCCCCCUCGCGCACCCCGGCCCCGCCUCACACGCGCGCCCGAGCGAGCCCCGGGCUCCCCUCGGGCCCAGCGUGGCGCAGGGGUCAGUGGUUCUCUCGGGUCUCGGGACAGGUGAGCACCCUGAUGAAGGCCACGGUCCUGAUGCGGCAGCCUGGGCGGGUGCAGGAGAUCGUGGGCGCCCUCCGCAAGGGCGGCGGAGACCGGUUACAGAUUUCUCAAUAUGGUCAUGCUGCUUCCUCUAAUUGGACAGAAGGCGCCCACACCAGUACCUAGGGCCUUAUCCUCCCCAAGCCAGCGGCUCCCCAGUGAUUUCUGAUUUUGACAUGACCUUGAGCAGGUUUGCAUAUAAUGGAAAGCGAUGCCCUUCUUCUUACAAUAUUCUGGAUAAUAGCAAGAUCAUCAGUGAGGAGUGUCGGAAAGAGCUCACAGCGCUCCUUCACCACUAUUACCCAAUUGAGAUCGACCCACACCGGACCGUCAAGGAGAAGCUACCUCAUAUGGUGGAAUGGUGGACCAAAGCACACAAUCUCCUAUGUCAGCAGAAGAUUCAGAAGUUUCAGAUAGCCCAGGUGGUUAGAGAGUCCAAUGCAAUGCUCAGGGAGGGAUAUAAGACCUUCUUCAACACACUCUACCAUAACAACAUUCCCCUUUUCAUCUUUUCUGCGGGCAUUGGUGAUAUCCUGGAAGAAAUUAUCCGACAGAUGAAAGUGUUCCACCCCAACAUCCACAUCGUGUCUAACUACAUGGAUUUUAAUGAAGAUGGUUUUCUCCAGGGAUUUAAGGGCCAGCUCAUACACACAUACAACAAGAACAGCUCUGCGUGUGAGAACUCUGGUUACUUCCAGCAACUUGAGGGCAAAACCAAUGUCAUCCUGCUGGGAGACUCUAUCGGGGACCUCACCAUGGCCGAUGGGGUUCCUGGUGUGCAGAACAUUCUCAAAAUUGGCUUCCUGAAUGACAAGGUGGAGGAGCGGCGGGAGCGCUACAUGGACUCCUAUGACAUCGUGCUGGAGAAGGACGAGACUCUGGAUGUGGUCAACGGGCUACUGCAGCACAUCCUGUGCCAGGGGGUCCAGCUGGAGAUGCAAGGCCCCUGAAGGCGCAGGCUCCAGCCCGGCCUGCAGGCCGUGGUGAGGAGGGGCGCCUCCCCAGAGUCUGCUCCCCCGUGAACACAGAGCAGAGGCCAGGGUGGCCAGCAGUGGCUGGGUCCUUCCGCGCCCCUCCGUCCUCCUUUCCCUGAGCACCUUCAUCACCAGAGGCUUGAAGGAACCCCGCCAUGUGGCAGGGCACAGGCACUGUUCCUGGUGAACCUUGGACCACAGCAUGUCAGUGCUCUAGGGAUUGUCUACUCCAGGGAUUUUCUUCAAAAUUUUUAAACAUGGGAAGUUCAAACAAAUAUAAUGUGUGAAACAGAUCAAAAUUUUUAAAAUGAAAAAAAAGCUGCUCUGAUUCAGGGGAUGUGGGUGGGGGUAGAACCUGGACCUCUUGGCCCUGGGGGCACAUGGGAUGCUUCUAGGAACACAGUUUGAGAACCACCACAAAUUGGCCUGAGACCCCAUCCGA